AUACUUGAAAGUCCCACUUUAUGAACUAUUUUUUUUCAGAGUUCAUUUUUAGUGACAUAAUCAUUGCCACAAAUUUCCUUUUCCUUCUAAGAAUUUGUCUCUGAAAGUGAUUUUGCAUUCUCAAGUUCGAUUAGGGGGGAGCCUUAAAAACAAUUUUGUGUGCUUAGUAUUGAGGAAGUGUUUAUAAAUUACUCUUUCUCCCUGGUCUAGUCUCAAGUAUAAUAAAAUAUCCAUUUCAAAUAGCUUUCUAAUGUCUUGUUAUAUUUGCCAAGUGAUUUAUAGGACAGAAAAUUAUAGUUUGCGUGUGUAAAGUUCAGAGAUAUUUUAGAGCUUGGAGCAGAGGAGAGGAGAGGUUUUAGGGUUAAAUUCAAGCCAUCAAUCUCCAAUUGUCUAAACACUACACGAAGUGGAGAUUCGAGGCAAUUAUCCGAAUAAUUGGGGGGGGGGGGCACUUUCGCCUGAAUUAUCUAGAUAAAAGAGCGACACAGGAGAAUGUCAGUGGCCCUGAAGGCCCUGCCUCGGAUCUCCACGGUCGCGCGAAUUCGGGCAAUUUUUCUGAAGGUUCUCAGACUCGGGGAUGGGGGAGGAAGGGGACGUUUCUAGAAGAAACUUAAAGGGGGCUCGCGCCGCACGACUGUAGGUGGAGGGCGUGCGCCGCGGGACGCCCCAGCCGAGUCUGAUAAAGCCCCGAAGCCGAUCUAAGGUCAAUAAACCAGGCGGCGUCAGGCUUGGGCCGAGGGCCGGGAGGAGAGGAGAGUGGAGCCCUCUCAGGCUGGCGGCGGAAUGAAAAGGAACCCCGACUGCUGGGGUCCGAGCCCUGGGCCGCUUGCGGGGCGCGCAGCCGGGGAGAGGAGCUGGGCGCGCGGCCUGGGCCCCCCACCUGCCCGACCCCAGGGCAGCCAAGCACCCGCGGCCUUAAAAGUAUCCCGGCGAGCCCUGAGGGGGCCGGGUCCUGGGCGAACAGUCCUAGCCCUGCACUGAGGUUGGAAAAGCGAACGGAAAGUGACAUUUUUACAGGGGCGAGGUUGGGAUCGGGAGGGAGAUGGUGACCCCCGAAUAAUGGAAACGCAGAAGCCUCAGAGACACCAGCAACAGAUAGAGAAGUGUCCCUAAGAGGGGAAAAUGAGGAAGAGGGUAACAGUAUUGUUAACUGGCCAUGAAUUUUAAUCCCUGUUGUGUGUCGCCGAAUAGUUUACAAACUCUUUUUGCACUGGGGUUUUGUUUCUCCCACUCCCCGCAUGAUGAGAAGAAAGAAAGAUUGGGAGAAGUUAAUCAGCUCAAAGUCACAUCGCCGGGGUCUCCUGCCAGGGGGCUUGGACCAGUUGCUAAAGGACUUCCCGCCGGAGAAGGUCUUCCCAAGAGAGAUUCCCACCCAGAGCGCGCAGCCCGCGGGGAAAACAUAACGCGCGCCUGUAAAUGACGCCGCUCCCACCUAGGCCGCUCUGGGGCCGCUUAACGUCCGGAAUGUCCCGACCCCCGGCUCAAUCUUUGGUGCAAAGCCUGAGUGGGCAGGCGGGAGACCAGGCGGUGCCGGUGGAGCGGGCUACUUCAGCAGCGCGAGGCUCGGAAGAUCCCCGCGGACAGGCGCGACAACGGGCCCUGGAGCCGGGGAAUCUCUGCAAGUAACUAACCAGGCCCCUCGGAUUCAUUGCCACUUUCCCGCCCUCGGCCCACGAGGCUGAGGAGCUCCCUCUCAUCGCCUCUCCGUUCCUGGCAAGGCCGAAGCCGGUUUGCUUUGGAUGCAUUUCGAUCAAUCUGGCGCCACAUGGGCCAGGUCACCUCGGACGGGUGUCGCGCCGACGUCCUUCGUGGUCGCACGCUGGUGGGCCAGGAAGCCCAGGCCAUGCCCAGCCGGGUCCGAGCGGCGGUCGGUGGCGUGACCUCUUGCCACGCCUGGCGCUGCUGGGAACGUGUCUCGGGUCGCCCUUUGCGUCAGAGACCCCCCCCUUGGGGAGACCGGAAUCCUCCAGCCGCUGCGCACGGAUACCCUGGGCGGCGAGGAGAGCCCGGCUUCUGCGCACCCCUCUCCAGAUGCGAGGUGCUCACCCGCCCCUCGCCCUGCUCACCCCGACGCCUCGGUCCCCACGCUCUGGGCAGCAAGACACAUAGCGAAGCCCCUGACCCAUUUCUUCUCAGUUGCGACCCCCUGUGUGAGACCCCUAAAGAGGCCAAGGAUCACAAACCUUCGGGGGUUAGUCACAGGCCCUGGCCCGCGCGGGAUCUGGAGGCAGAGAUUUCUCGACGUUUGGGGACUUACAGCUCGUCUGGGAGCGACUGGAUUCCCAGGCCUCCGCACGCUGAGGUUCCGGGGAAGAGCACUGUCUUCACCACUUCUCGACCUGCGCCCCAACCCAUCAAAUUUCCAGCACUCGUCCCCCUAGGUCUCAUAAAAACUCCUGGCAGACCCUUCCGGGAUCACGCGUGGCUCAACUCGGGGGCCGUAGCUACGAUCCCCGCGCAGACGCCGGAAUCCGGGGCCCGGUCCCCGCGCGGGGUGCGGCGCUCGCGGGGGGGUGGAUGGGGUCGGUCCCUCUCGGGAACGGCUGCUGUUGUUUCUUUAGAUACUGAAUAUAAUUUCUCCCUCCUCCACCCCACUCGCUGUUCUUAACAAUUUUAUUUAUUGGUUUACUAUUGUCUUGUGAACGUUUCUUGUCUCCUCCUUGCCUUUUUUCAUCCCCUUUCUCUCUUCAUUUCUCUCUUUUUCCUUAAUUCUGUUGCAAAGUUUCCUUUUCUUGCUUAAUCAAAAUUCUCCCCGCUUACUUUGUUCUUUGCCCACAGCAUUCGUUCUUCUUUUCUCCUUGCCUGCCUGUCUUCUUUCCCGCUGUUCUUGGCCGUGGGCAGACCCGGCUGAUGUAAGGACUGCAGCUUUUCCCUGGCAUACUAUGCGCCUUCAGAUGUGGUCUGCGUCUGCCUGGGUCUCUUCCCACCUCAAUCUGAGAUCCUUGCCCCUCACAAUAAAUUCGUUUUUAUUCAUUCUGA